GAGCGACGCAGCCGGGACGGUAGCUGCGGUGCGGACCGGAGGAGCCAUCUUGUCUCGUCGCCGGGGAGUCAGGCCCCUAAAUCGAAGAAGCCCUGGCGCGCCCUCCCCCCCUCCCGGGUCUGGUAGGGCGAAGGAACGGGCGUGCGGUCGAUCGAGCGAUCGGUUGGCGGCUCUUUCUCCUGCUCUGGCAUCCAGCUCUUGGGGCGCAGGCCCGGCCGCCGCGGCGCGCGCCCGGUGGCCGUUGGCGCUCGCGCCGCGUCUUUCUUCUCGUACGCAGAACUCGGGCGGCGGCCUAUGCGUUUGCGAUUCGACGAGGAGUCGUCCGGGUGGUCGGCGGCGGCGGGCAGCUGCUCCGCCCCGCUCCGGGGGAGGCGGCGGCGGCAGCGGCCGCGGGAUUUGGAGCGGCCGGGGAGGCGGGGGUGGCCGGGGCCGGCUUGGAGGCCUGGCGCCACCCUUCGGGGCCUGCAAGGACCCAGUUGGGGGGGCAGGAGGGGGCCGGAGGAUGGUUGGUUGUGGGAUUUCUACUUUGCCUUUUCCUCCUUAUGCCGCCUUAGUGAGGGGCGGGAGCUCUGGCGGCAGCCCCGGGGUGGGGAGACGAGCUCCGGAGUCGGAAGAGCUGGGUUUUCUUCCGGGCCUAGCCACCAGUUGGCGGAGUGACCUUAGGCGAGUCACUCUGUAAUUUGUCUGCGCCUCAGUUUCCUCCUCUGCCUAUCAAUGUGUGUGGGGUUGAAAUCGCUUUGUAAACUAUAAAGCGUGGGUGUACGUAAAGGAUGGUUAUUGUUUAUAAUUUUUUUUGAGUUGUAAGAAAACUUAGCAGUUCCCCAAUCCUUGGGUUUUGAACCUGGGAACCUUGGAUUGGAGUUGGGGAUCCCCAAACUUCCUGAAAUUGUGGGAAUGUGCGGUUUGGGGGAAUGAUGGGAAUUUGUGGGAAUGUGCGUUUUAGGGGAAUGAUGAUCCAUCGCUAGCAAGUUUUCCAAGGGGGCUGUGACCCAGAAGAGUUAAGAAUCACAAUUUCUUCAUGCUACAGAGAGGAAACUGAGGCCUAGAUGUCAUUUGGGACCCUUCACAACCAUUUUGAAGCCCUGUUUGAGUCCCUGGGAUAUGUGAGCUGUUUCUAUGCAUAAUGGAUAUUCGGGGUUAACAACAGUCCCCUGCUUGGCUUCUAUUCUGAAUCCUUUUCUUUCACCAUGGGGUGCCUGAAGGGUGGCUGAUGCAUAUGGUACAAUGGCACCCAGUGUAAAGCAGCUACAAUUAGGAGUGGAUGUGUUCUGUAGCAUCCUAUUUAAAUAAGCCUAUUUUAUCCUUUGGCCCGUCAACUCUGUUAUCUGCUGCUUGUACUGGUGCCUGUACUUUUCUGACUCUCAUUGACCAUAUUCCACGACCAUGGUUGUCAUCCAUUACUUGAUCCUACUUUACAUGUCUAGGCUGUGUGGUUGGUGGUGAAUAGGCUUCUUUUUACAUGGUGCUGCCAGCCCAGCUAAUUAAUGGUGCACGUGGACUUUUAGCAAGCGGGCUCACUGGAAGAGACUGAACCUGGCAUGGAAUUCCUGAAGAUGUUUGGGGUUUUUUUCUUUCUUAAUCGAAAGUUAACAUUGUCUGAAAAGUUUUGUUAGAACUACUGCGGAACCUCAAAAUCAGUAGAUUUGGAAGUGAUUCAAAGCUAAACUUUUUCCUUGGCCCUCCUUGUGUUCUAAUUGCUUGCAAGUGUAAUACUAGGAUGUCCAAGAUGCCAGUUUUUGCUUCUUUGUUAGUUGUCAGCUGCUUUUAUCAAAUUUCAGGCCAUUAUCCAACAAACACUAUAAAAAUGUUUGAACAAUUGGAUUUCAAACAUUUUCGUUUUGUGGAGUGGUGCUCACCAAGUGGUACAGCCCUAAGCAAGUGAACACAAACACAUUUAAGUGUAUUUUGUCUGAUUAGAUGUUAGCCAGUUAUGCUAUUUCAUUCAAAUGUCUGAAAAAAUCAAUUGACUAUUCCCUUUUCCUAAAGGGCAGAGACAGAUAAUCUCACUUCCAGAGAAAUGACUUGGAGAAAAAAAAGUGUUGGUCUUUUUGCUCUUUUGUAAUUAAAUCCGGAUGUACCUCAAAAGACUUAAGACUGUGGUGAUAAGAUGCUUUCCUCAGCAGAAAGGAGGGAAAAAAAACAACUGGAACUCAAAGCUUGAAAUUCUGUGGCAAAACAUGAGAUGUCCAGGAUUGGAGGUUGAAAAGAUUUCACUACAGUGUUCUGCAAUAGUUGGAGCAGAUAACUUUCAGUGUAGCCACAGCCAUGGACUCCAGAUUUCCAGAUUUUCAAGACCUGGACCUGGAACCCGAAAGAGCUUGUCACGAUGCGGCAGGAACACUGGAGGUAGAUUUUUUUUUAUUUUUGAAUUUUGGGACUGUUGACCUUGCUGUGAGAAAAGAGACAACGACUGAGCAAGCACUACCACCAGCACUGUUACUGGGAAUUAGAAGACCUGAGUUUCUGUCCAGACCCUCAGUGCAAACUGAGGAUGCUCCAUCCAAAGUGAAUUAUGAUAGCAGACUCCUUGAAAGCAGGGUCCUUGUUUAGUGCAUCUUUGCCCACAUACACCACAACAUAUCAAGAUGCAUUUAUUAGGAAGGAGGAGUUUAGAGAGCAGGCUAUCAGAAUAACCACUCAUCCUGUGCCUCCUGAUUGCUGAGUGUUCACCUGGACCUUCUGACUACCUUCCCUGUGCUAUUCCAUCAGCCUACAGACCUGGUACCUGGAUUUUUGCCCGAGAUGAUUCCUACCACCUUACUACUGACGAAGACACCCAUUCCAGUGGACCACUGUGACCCAGGAGGCAUUCAGCCAUCAUGAUGUGGCCUUUACCUCCACUCCUGUCUUGUUCUACCCAGAUUCAGCACAGCCCUUUAUAGUGAAGUCAGAGUCCUCAAGCCAAAUAGCUAAAGCUGUUUUAUCACAACAAAGGCCUAGUUUGUUCCAUGAGUGUGCAUUUCAUUUCUUCAGUUAAAGCCUUCAGAGACACACAAUAAAUUUGGACCAGGGGAUUUUUUAGUUAUUAAUGCUCUCUGAAGAAAGGCAACAUCUUUUUGAGAGCAGCAUUGGACCACACCCCACAAUCUCAAAUGAUUGAAAUUCAUGAACAUCUAGGAUCCCGUGAAGGUCACUGGACCCUGUUUUUUCUACUUCAAAUCCUGUAGUAGCCUACUGAAUGAGAAAACAUAUUCUGACCCAUUGGGAUCAAAUCAAAGGCACAGUGAACUCCUCAUAGCAUCUUCUUUGGAAUUACUCAGGAACCAGAACUUUUUACACAAAUGUAAGAAAUUCUACCAAGGAGUCCCCUUACCUAACAGCAUCUCACAAGGCUGCACCAGAUUCCAGAAAAGGCUUCUCUUGAUACAUCAAGCAUUUUGUGACCGACUUAUUCUUAGAUCAUUGGUUUUCCAAAGGCUUUGUGGCCAUGAAGCCCUUUGAGUGAAAACUGUGCAGAAGCCCAGAGUAAAAGUGAAGCUGCUCUGGAUGAAGUAGUGAAGCAAGAGUAGGGGCCUGAAUCCUGCUACAACUAUCUUCCUUUACCACCGUGGUGACACCUAAGGGGACUUCCUUACAACACCUUGAACUCUUCCGAACACAGUUUGAAAACCACUGCCCCAGACAGCAAUAUGUUUGACCUGAAUGGCAUUCCAAUCUUUUCUGUACCUCCACUCAGCACAGUUCAUGUUCAGUAGAUGCUGAACAUUCUUAGAAAUACUGUGUGUGAACUUAGAAAAGUGCAAGAAGACAGGCAUGUCUUUGACCCCAGGAAUGAUCAUUUGCUGAAGAUGGUGUCAAGUGAACCUAGAUUAACAGCCCUCCACUCCAGAUGGAUAUCCAGUGAUUCCUAGAAUGGGAUAUAGCCAGAGAACAAUUCUAUGCACCCUACACUGACAGACUCCCUUAAGCAACACCAGAUGCUCUACUGGUACUUGAAGUACAUGACUUUGAAGUCUUGACCCUCCAUGAAUACCUGAAUUAUCAGCAAGCGGGUUUUGAAGCUGGUGCCUCAUUGAGGCCAUAUUAGAGCAACUUGUACAUUUGACCUCUUGUUAUCAGCCAUGGUACUCUACUUCGUGUGCAAGAGAUAACUAUGAAAGCCAAAUUCAAAUACUGGCAACAUUUCCUAAAGGGGCUCAAUAUCUAUCAUUCGUCUUCUUUUCCAAACUACACAUCACUGUAUGACUCAACCAGUAGCAGUUAUAUUGCCCCUUGGUUUUUAUUCAGUUUAACUACUGUUUCCAAGAUAAAUGAGCUAAUAAGCUUUAAAAAAAAAAAAAAAAAAGGCUGAAUUCUUUUUUCUUCAUCACUGGCAUAUCUGCCUAUUCUCCAGAAUUAUUAUGACUAUUCAGCUCACUUUAACAGUUGAACUUCAAGCGACAAUCUUUGAACACCCCUUCUCAUGUGAUUUAAAAUGAAACCAUUUGGAAAAGUUUCUUCUAGCCAGUAAUAGAUUUUUUUUUUAAUUGCUCUGCCUUGUGCCGAGAGAUGUUCUUUUAAGAUGAAUCUUUUGAUGUCUGAUACCACCAAAUAUAGGUGGUAGGGAGAGUUGGAGGCUGGCCCUUUGAGCAGGCCAUUAGCUUACUUGCUGGGCAUUUCCGAUAGCUUAUUGCCUACCUUUUUGCUGGAAACAAACUGAUUUGAAAAACAAAAUCUAUGAAGACUGCAGCUAAGGAUUUUAUCGGUAGACUUAAGAGCUUUUGUCCUUGUGGAUAUUUUAGUGGAACCACAUCAGUCUCAAUACUGUCAUUUUACACUGACUCAGAGCAGCUGACUUCAUUCCUUGCCAUGAUAUAUAUUUAAGGCAGGCAUUGUAACAGACAUAAAGACAACUUAUCUGUUUCAGCAGGAAGGAUUCAGUUUAUGAACUCUCAGACCAGAUCAUGUUGAACAAGGAGACUUUGAUGUGUGUCAUGAGAAAACUCAUUCUUUACUUCCCAGUCAAUUUAAAGGCCAGCUAUCCUGAGCUACUCGAAUGAAUGCACUGGUUAAACAUUGGAAAUAGUUUGUUUAUAUCCUUGUCUCUCUCUAGGCCAAUUGUGAUUACAUGACUCGACUCUACAUCUCGUCAAACAAGGCCUAGGUCUGGUUGCUGUAGACUGCUCGCCCUCAACAAAUAAAAUCUGGUUGACUAGCCUCCUUGUAUAUACAACUAUUAUUUGUUAAGAAGAAAUUAUCGUCAAUUUUCUACUACCUUCCAAUUGUCAGCUCUUUUUUUCCUCUCUGGUUUUUCCUAUACUUUACAGAAAAAGACAUUGAUCUAUACUGCCAUUCCCUCUAAUCCUGCCAUACUCAGUCAAAAGGAAUGACUUAAGAUGAAGAUGAUCAUCUGCUCGAGUCUAAAAUAUACAUUGUAUAUAAGAAUUGGUGAUUAGAAAAGCAAAAAACCUAAAACUUAAAUCUAGGAGUCUGUAUACUGUCUCCAUGUCUCCAUGCCUCAGAUCUCAUCUAAAUCUUUGAACAGCACCAUUCAACCAAUCUGAGGCCUUGACUUGCUUGUAAGAUGAUUCUCAGAGAUCGGCUGAGUUAAAAAAGAUGACGACUUGAUUACCAAAGAAAGUAGGGCCAACUUUGACAAAUCUGGCUCUGCUGACCCUGUCACUCCCAGAUGUAGCAUAGACUCCUAAACAGAACCUCAAGUCUGAUUGAGGAUAAGGCCUUCUCCUGAGCUGAAAGUUCUUUGGCAGAUGAGCAAGAAACUGAAAGCUGAUGUACCUGACUGGCUCUGUAAGAUCAGAAAACUGUAUCCAGAAUAAGCCCUAUGGAUUAACCCCUGAGUACCCAGAGUAAAAACUAAUUUACAGAACUUCCUUAUUGAUCUGCUGGUUCUUCCAGAUCAUAUUCUGGCUAUUGGUAUGGCUGGCCUUUCUGAAGGUACCCUGCUUGUCUAUUUUCCUGACUCAGCUCUUGCCUGCCUUUUUCACAUGUUGCUGCAAUUAGACUCACCGUGAGGACUACAGUCAAUUUCAGUCUAUCUUGUGCCCAAUACAACAAGGAUUUUUAAUAGUAACAACCCACACCUCACCCACUAGGACUCAAUGUUCACAACAGGAAGGACCAUUGCUGCAUACUCCUUGACCAGCAACUUUUUUGAAGAUAUUUUUAAGUGCAGAGUAGGCCUCUAUUCCUGUAUGUAAUUGUUCAUUUUCAGCACCUGGAACCUCAUCUAUCGGGUCUGGAAGGAAUACAGCAGUUCGAAAGCCGCGUCCAUUUCUCUCCUUCAGUAGUGCAGAAAUGAGUCCGAUUCACCAGUACACACAGAACUGUACCAGUUCAACCUAGCAAAAGAAGAAAAGUUUCCACUGUACUUAAAAUUUACAGCUGACUCAAAUUGCCUCACAGAAUUAUUUGAUGUAGAAGGCUAGUUGUCUUACUUCAGAUCAGCAGGACAGUUGGGCUCUCAGACUCAUGACCACUGAGUUUGCUUGUGUUGAAACUGUGGUUUCAUCCAACAUAUGCUAUUGGACAUGAUUAUUAUUCCAUUCAAAUGGAUUACAGACUUCUUGAGGACAGGACAAACUUAUCUCUCAUGGUGUUUUUUUAGAAUACUUUUAUAACCAAGGAAGAAACCAUGCCAGCUGUUACCAUUCAACUUCUUAAGCAGAGAUUAAGCUUUUUCAUAUCUGUUCUUAUCCUGGACAUCAGUAGUUUUUAAUUGCCCAGCAUCCGUUCCAUCUUGUAACAACUCCCUGAUGUUUCUUAAAACCACCUCUUCCUAUUUUCAGUCUGUGGUUUGGACAGUCUGACCCAACCUUGAGCUUUGUGGGUGAACAUGUAAUUCAGACCUCAUCAAUCAGCAAAUCCAUCUGAACUGUGGAGGAGAAGCUCUCUUUACUGAGGGUGCUUUAGCUUUGUAGGAUGAAAACCUCAAACUAACAGGGCCUACCAUGUAGAGAAUGAAGCCAGUGCAGGGGAAAGCAGAGCCAAAAUAUGGAGAGACUUGAAUCCUGAUGACAGCGUUUGUGCCCCUGGAUCCAACCGUGCCUGAAGCUAGAAUAUCCCCUGGACUUUUCAGUUAUGUGAACCAAUAAAUACCCUUUUUUGCUUAAGUUACUUUGAGUUGGGUUUCUGUUACUUGAAAUUGAAUCCACACUAAUAUAUCUACCAACAUUGAGACUUGACAGAUCCAAGUAUUUAUUAAGCUAGAGGUCAUGGUCACUGAAAUUACUUUCCAAAGUGGAAGACAAAAUGAAACAGGAACUGAGGGAAUAUUUAAGAUCCCACAGAAGCGUAAAAAUGACAUGGUAGAAAGUAAUAGAAAACCUAAAUGUCUGUCAUUAAAGGAUAGGUUAAGGUGUGGUUCAGCCAUAUAGGAAUAUCUCGUAUCUGUUAAAAUGAAUAAAGUACAUUCAUUGUGUAUGGAAAAAUGGCCAUGAUACAUUAGGUGAAACAAGUUAUUAAUAGAAAAGUGUACAGUGUGAACUCAUUUUAAAAUGUGUGUGCUUAUGUUUAUAAAUGCAUAGAAAGGUCUAUUCACAGCUUUCUUUGAACAGUGUAGAUCACAUGAAACUUUCAACUUUAUACAUUUCUGUAUUAAUAUUUUACACUACCCACAUUAUUUUUAAACUUUAUUUUAAAUAAAGAAUUUUUAAAAUUAAA